AGCACUGCAGGGCUCUGGGCGGGAAGGCUAACCUGGUGCGGAGCCAGCCUGGGUCUCAGCCCCGCGUACGGCCUUUCACGAGUCUUCAAGCCUUCAGGCUUUCUUCUAGUCAAGAUGAGUGAUAAACCAGACUUGUCGGAAGUGGAGAAGUUUGACAGGUCAAAACUGAAGAAAACUAAUACUGAAGAAAAAAAUACUCUUCCCUCAAAGGAAACUAUCCAGCAGGAGAAAGAGUGUGUUCAAACAUCAUAAAAUGGGGAUCUCCUCCAAAGAGCAGAUUUCAGCAUUGCCUGACAGUCUUGGUUUUAGGCUUGUUUUUUUGUAAACCUGUGUGUUUGUAGAGAUUUCAGACAUCUUCUGAUUUCUUCUCACCUAUAUUCCCUGGUUAAGAGGUCAGGGGUAGUGAAUGUUUCCUUAAGUUCCUUUUUAAACUUCCCAUUGGUAUGUAAAUUCCAAAUGGCAGAUGCUGUCAAUAACCUUGCCAUGGAUGACCUUUGUGUAGGUAGUCCUUGCACCUCAUGCAGGAUAAGCCAAUUUUAACUUUCUACAAUGGGUGCCUCAAUAGUUUCAUAAUCUUCAUGAAGUUGCAUCCUUUGGCAGCUUCUUACAGUUUAUUUUCACUUCCAAUGUAGCAAUAAAAUAAUAAAUAUAA